AGACGUCGCACCCGGAAGUAAAGCGGCUCCGUGACGGAGCGGCGGUGCGCGCGGCAGGGCCCGGAGUAUCCCGCUUUCUUUGGAGGAAACCACCGCAUCAGAUCUGCGCUGCGGCAGAGGCAGGCAAGUCCCUAGCGUGGAGGGGCAGCAUGCUGGCAGCACUUGGGGAGGCGGUGCGCUAAGGGAUUCACGCUGUAACUGGGACCGCAGCAGGGAACUACAAUUUCCAUAGUGCUCCGCGCCCUCCCAGCUGGCUCUACUGCCGGCGACGGCGUGGUACACGCUGGGAUUUGUAGUCUUACAUGGCUUUGCGCCUCCUACCUGGAAGGCGGGCCAGCGAUUGGUACCAGUUCAGACAUGGGUACACGUUGACAGGCCGCCGGCCGUCGACUGGCAUGUUGUGACCAUUCCUGGUGCUGGUCUUGGUACUGUUCUUUCCUACCAUAACUUAUUGGAAGAGGGUGGCAUUCCUGCCUUGCAGCCUUUUCUCCAGUGAGGAGUGAACAGUGGGCACCUGAGAUCCUGGCCCACGCUACUAUGCUUUCAGGCUACAACCACUAGCACGGCUGACGAUGGCCCUUUCUGCGGAGACCGAGUCACACAUCUACCGAGCUCUGCGUACUGCUUCUGGCGCUGCCGCCCACCUUGUGGCCCUGGGCUUUACCAUCUUUGUGGCUGUGCUUGCCAGGCCUGGCUCCAGCCUGUUCUCCUGGCACCCGGUGCUUAUGUCUUUGGCUUUCUCCUUCCUGAUGACCGAGGCACUACUGGUGUUUUCUCCUGAGAGUUCGCUGCUGCACUCCCUCUCACGGAAAGGCCGAGCACGCUGCCACUGGGUGCUGCAGCUGCUGGCCCUGCUGUGUGCACUGCUGGGCCUCGGCCUUGUCAUCCUCCACAAAGAGCAGCUUGGCAAAGCCCACCUGGUUACGCGGCAUGGGCAGGCAGGGCUGCUGGCUGUGCUGUGGGCAGGGCUGCAGUGCUCAGGUGGGGUGGGGCUGCUCUACCCCAAGCUGCUGCCCCGAUGGCCCCUGGCGAAGCUCAAGCUAUACCAUGCUACUUCUGGGCUGGUGGGCUACCUGCUGGGUAGUGCCAGCCUCUUGCUGGGCAUGUGCUCACUCUGGUUCACUGCCUCUGUCACUGGUGCAGCCUGGUACCUGGCUGUAUUAUGCCCUGUCCUCACCAGCUUGGUCAUUAUGAACCAGGUGAGCAAUGCCUACCUAUACCGCAAGAGGAUCCAACCAUGAGCUCUUCCCAGCCUAGGGGAAGCCUGGAUUUGCCCCUCCAUGUAGGAGCUGGGCCUAGGGACCUGUUGAACUCUCUCAGCUGAGUCAGGGGACACCUCAGGCACUGGGACAGUUGGGCAUUUGGAGGCCCGUGUGUGAAUUCCUGCUCCUCAUGCUGGAGUGCCUCCCAUUUCCUUCCCCUUUCUCUGUCAUCCCAGAGGAACAUAGGCAUCAUGUGUCUGGAUGAAGCUGGGGCUGCAAGACUGCCUCUCCUGCAAGGCAGCUCAUACUUGUACUGUAUGUUCAGAAAUUUUAGGAGAGAAAAAAGUAAAAAAUUUGUAAAAAA